GGAAGAGCUUCCAUGGAGUCAGGGCAGCCGGCUCGACGGAUUGCCAUGGCGCCGCUGCUGGAGUACGAGCGACAGCUGGUGCUGGAACUGCUCGACACUGACGGGCUAGUAGUGUGCGCCCGCGGGCUCGGCGCGGACCGGCUCCUCUACCACUUUCUCCAGCUGCACUGCCACCCAGCCUGCCUGGUGCUGGUGCUCAACACGCAGCCGGCCGAGGAGGAGUAUUUUAUCAAUCAGCUGAAGAUAGAAGGAGUUGAACACCUCCCUCGCCGUGUAACAAAUGAAAUCACAAGCAACAGUCGCUAUGAAGUUUACACACAAGGUGGUGUUAUAUUUGCGACAAGUAGGAUACUUGUGGUUGACUUCUUGACUGAUAGAAUACCUUCAGAUUUAAUUACUGAAAUUCUUCCUCUGACAUGCCAGAAACACCCCACCCCAGGGCCUGUGCCCUCACUGUCCCCUCAGCCUGGCAGCCUGGAACUCUCUUGGCCCAGAUGGUCACAAGGCUCCAUCCAGCCUUUAUUCAGAUACCACCUUGGCAUCUUGGUGUAUAGAGCCCACAGAAUAAUCGAGUCUUGUCAAGAAGCAUUCAUCUUGCGCCUCUUUCGCCAGAAAAACAAACGUGGUUUUAUUAAAGCUUUCACAGACAAUGCUGUUGCCUUUGAUACUGGUUUUUGUCAUGUGGAAAGAGUGAUGAGAAAUCUUUUUGUGAGGAAACUGUAUCUGUGGCCAAGGUUCCAUGUAGCAGUAAACUCAUUUUUAGAACAGCACAAACCUGAAGUUGUAGAAAUCCAUGUUUCUAUGACACCUACCAUGCUUGCUAUACAGACUGCUAUACUGGACAUUUUAAAUGCAUGUCUAAAGGAACUAAAAUGCCAUAACCCAUCGCUUGAAGUGGAAGAUUUAUCUUUAGAAAAUGCUAUUGGAAAACCUUUUGACAAGACAAUCCGCCAUUAUCUGGAUCCUUUGUGGCACCAGCUUGGAGCCAAGACUAAAUCCUUAGUUCAGGAUUUGAAGAUAUUACGAACUUUGCUGCAGUAUCUCUCUCAGUAUGAUUGUGUCACAUUUCUUAAUCUUCUGGAAUCUCUGAGAGCAACGGAAAAAGCUUUUGGUCAGAAUUCAGGUUGGCUGUUUCUUGACUCCAGCACCUCGAUGUUUAUAAAUGCUCGAGCAAGGGUUUAUCAUCUUCCAGAUGCCAAAAUGAGUAAAAAAGAAAAAAUAUCUGAAAAAAUGGAAAUUAAAGAAGGGGAAGAAACAAAAAAGGAACUGGUCCUAGAAAGCAACCCAAAGUGGGAGGCACUGACUGAAGUAUUAAAAGAAAUUGAGGCAGAAAAUAAGGAGAGUGAAGCUCUUGGUGGUCCAGGUCAAGUACUGAUUUGUGCAAGUGAUGACCGAACAUGUUCCCAGCUGAGAGACUAUAUCACUCUUGGAGCGGAGGCCUUCUUAUUGAGGCUCUACAGGAAAACCUUUGAGAAGGAUAGCAAAGCUGAAGAAGUCUGGAUGAAAUUUAGGAAGGAAGACAGUUCAAAGAGAAUUAGGAAAUCUCACAAAAGACCUAAAGACCCCCAAAACAAAGAACGGGCUUCUACCAAAGAAAGAACCCUCAAAAAGAAAAAACGGAAGUUGACCUUAACUCAAAUGGUAGGAAAACCUGAAGAACUGGAAGAGGAAGGAGAUGUCGAGGAAGGAUAUCGUCGAGAAAUAAGCAGUAGCCCAGAAAGCUGCCCGGAAGAAAUUAAGCAUGAAGAAUUUGAUGUAAAUUUGUCAUCGGAUGCUGCUUUCGGAAUCCUGAAAGAACCCCUCACUAUCAUCCAUCCGCUUCUGGGUUGCAGCGACCCCUAUGCUCUGACAAGGGUACUACAUGAAGUGGAGCCAAGAUACGUGGUUCUUUAUGACGCAGAGCUAACCUUUGUUCGGCAGCUUGAAAUUUACAGGGCGAGUAGGCCUGGGAAACCUCUGAGGGUUUACUUUCUUAUAUACGGAGGUUCAACUGAGGAACAACGCUAUCUCACUGCUUUGCGGAAAGAAAAGGAAGCUUUUGAAAAACUCAUAAGGGAAAAAGCAAGCAUGGUUGUCCCUGAAGAAAGAGAAGGCAGAGAUGAAACAAACUUAGACCUAGUAAGAGGCACAGCAUCUGCAGAUGUUUCCACUGACACUCGGAAAGCCGGUGGCCAGGAACAGAAUGGUACACAGCAAAGCAUAGUUGUGGAUAUGCGUGAAUUUCGAAGUGAGCUUCCAUCUCUGAUCCAUCGUCGGGGCAUUGACAUUGAACCCGUGACUUUAGAGGUUGGAGAUUACAUCCUCACUCCAGAAAUGUGCGUGGAGCGCAAGAGUAUCAGUGAUUUAAUCGGCUCUUUAAAUAACGGCCGCCUCUACAGCCAGUGCAUCUCCAUGUCCCGCUACUACAAGCGUCCCGUGCUUCUGAUUGAGUUUGACCCUAGCAAGCCUUUCUCUCUCACUUCCCGAGGUGCCUUGUUUCAGGAGAUCUCCAGCAAUGACAUUAGUUCCAAACUCACUCUUCUUACACUUCACUUCCCCAGACUACGGAUUCUCUGGUGCCCCUCUCCUCAUGCAACGGCGGAGUUGUUUGAGGAGCUGAAACAAAGCAAGCCACAGCCUGAUGCGGCGACAGCACUGGCCAUUACAGCAGAUUCUGAAACCCUUCCCGAGUCAGAGAAGUAUAAUCCUGGUCCCCAAGACUUCUUGUUAAAAAUGCCAGGGGUGAAUGCCAAAAACUGCCGCUCCUUGAUGCACCACGUUAAGAACAUCGCAGAAUUAGCAGCCCUGUCACAAGACGAGCUCACGAGUAUUCUGGGGAAUGCUGCAAAUGCCAAACAGCUUUAUGAUUUCAUUCACACCUCUUUUGCAGAAGUCGUAUCAAAAGGAAAAGGGAAAAAGUGAACAGUGAUGGCUGUUUUCUUAUCCCAUGCCUGUACUUUUCAGCGGCUCCUUGCCAGACAUCAUAGGUCAUUAUUAAUUAUUGGUUUGCUAUUUCAUUCUUUUCCAAUGCUCUUAAUGAUUGUACGGUGGACCAGAAGCCAGGAUUCCUCUCUGAACUCUGCAGUUAGGCAUCACUUGAACUUGCCUGUGCCUGCUCUUUUUCCUCCCUGCACCGUCUAUGCCGGGCUUAGCAUGUUUCUUUUUAAAUGAGGUUUGUCAGGAUCAGGUAAAGUUCCUACAAGUGAUUACAGAAGGUAGAAACUUUACCUGAUCCUAACAGAUCUCAUUUAGAAAGGAAUAUGCUAAGCCUGGCAUGGACGGUGCAGGGAGGGAAAAGAGCAGGCACAAGAAAGCUACCAUUUUUAACAGUCCUUGUUAUCUAGUGCAACAUAAAUAACAGUCUUAAUUGCACUUAUACCCAUGUCCUGUGGCUCUCCAAAUCUGGUCUUUGCUGUUGUGUCUGCUGGACGCUUGAACUGAUGUUUGUGUAGGAAAUCAUGUUCUGACCCUUUGUCUACAAAGGAGCCUUCUGGAACACUGAGAAGAAACAUCUCUUUGCCAUUCCUGACCAGUUCUCUCUACCACAUUUUCUUCAGCUCCAUACUUCUGCCUGUCUGCUCUAAGGAAAUUUCAUGGAGCCUUCCUACUACUAAUUCAAGACAGUCUCCUCAAAAACUGGUUGACUAGUCUUCUAAUGACCCUAACAUAUGUAGCAUAUACUAUAAUUUCAUUGUUCCAAAUUAGUAUUUUUAAAGCAAAAUGAAUUACCUGUUUGCAAAAGUUAAUGAUGAAGGAGCUCUUAGAAUUCUCAAUUUUUGCACAUAUUCAGUCUCCUAAUAUCAGAGAUCCCUAAGUCCAGCUGGCUAGUUACAGAGUUUUUUCAGACUUCCUCGUUUCUCAGCUCUUAUAUCCUAAGACACCAGCAUCAUAUCCUCUAGAAAUACAACCUAAUUGGCAGUGAGCCGAGAUCGCACCACUGCACCCCUGCCUGGGCGACAGAGUGAGACUUUGUCUCUAUUACAAAAAGAAAAGAAAAGAAAUACAACCUAAGCUCACCUGCCUGUGAUUCCUCAUUUCUCACCAUCCUGUGCCAGGGUGGCUACUUCUCUCUGUGAGGACUCAAAUACAAGCCAAUGAGUGGCCCACUAAGCUUUUAAGAUUUGAUUUUCCUGCCUUGAGAUAAAAAGGAGUGUAGGUAAAUGAAAGAUCAAUGUAUGGAAUAUAUAAAAAUACGAAAGAAAUAUAUACGUUUAAAAAUCCAUAAAGAAAAAAAUCUCAUUCUAAACCUGAUUAAGUUGGCUUUUUACGUAAGUGUACAAAUAGGAUAUUCACAGCAUCUUUGUGCAGUUUUUAAACUUUUAUAUUUAAACAUUAUUAAGUUGGCUUUUGUUCACAUGUUGAGUAAUGGGUAGUAAAUUUUCUACCUCAGGAGCUGAUAUAGACAUCAGUUCUGCUAGCCAUAUCACAUAUUUUAAUGUUUCAUCAACAUCAGCUGUUUUUUUGUUUGCUACACUAUUUGAACUAAUAGACAGUGGAUCAUGUAACACAAAAUUGUCUUCAACUUUAACAAAAUUGUCAUUGUUAUUUUUUUUUGAGACAGAGUCUCCCUCUGUUGCCCAGGCUGGAGUGCAGUGGCGCAAUCUCGGCUCACUGCAACCUCGCCUGCUGGGUUCAAGCAGUUCUCCCACCUCAGCCUCCCAAGUAGCUGGGAUUAUAGGUGUGCACCACCAGACCCGGCUAAUUUUUGUAUUUUUAGUAGAGACGGGGUUUCACCAUGUUGGCCAGGCUGGUCUCAAACUACUGACCUCAGGUGAUCCACCCACCUUGGCCUCCCAAAGUGCUGAGAUAACAGGCGUGAGCCACCGCACCCACCCAACAAAAUUAUUUUUAACUGUCGUUUCUGAACUGAACCUCUCACAUUGGCAUCUUGAUUUAUUGGUACUUAACAGUAUAUAUGGAUUUUGAACUCUACACAAGGGUAUAACCAGAAUGAAUUGAGGGGUAUCAAGAACCAGAUUGGUUACAGUAGAACUCUGUAAGAUGAUGUGGAGAGUAAGGAAAAGGAGAAGAAAUAAAAAUUAGUUUAAGAUGGAAUAAAGAUUUGGGCUGCUAAUUUUUUCCCAGGAUUCAAAAUAUACCCGCUAGAAUGGAAAACAAAAAUUUGAAUGAUUACAACAUUAUCGUUAACAUUCAAUUUUGUAUUUAUUGUUUUAUUGAAUAUAGUUCAGAGUAUAUUAAAAUAGACCUACCACUUCAAAUGAUAAUGAUUAUUAUAAUGUCUCUUCACCCUAUUCUAGCACUUCUGCUUGCAGUAUGUGGUUUCUAUUUUUUUCCUCUUGUAUAAUUCCACUUGCUUUUAAUUGUUGUUUCAUUAUAUAAAAGGAACAUCUUCCCAUAGCAUAUUCUAUGAAAGGGGUUUCAUUCCAAGUUGAGUUUUCAAAAAAAAGGUCUUCCUAAAGCUACCAUUUUCAACCGUCCUUGUUAUCUAGUACAACAUAAAUAACAGUCUUAAAAAUUGCACUAAUACCAGUGCCCCCCUGGCUCUCCAAAUCUGUUCUUUGCUCUUGUAUCUGCUGGACGCUUGAAGACAGGUGCACUGUCUCGUAUGUAUUUGAAUUAUGAACAGUAAUUUCUAAUGAAUUCUAAAAUGGUCAUUGUAAGUGAAAGCCUCUCGCUACCACUUCCUCUUCCAACUACAUAAAUAUAUUUCAAUGUAUUUCCAGUUUUGGAAAGUUUUCAAUACAUACAUCAAGUGUUUACUUAGAUUUUUAUAAAAAUUUUUUUUACAAUCUAAUAAUCUUUGGUAAAGGAACUAGAGAUGCAUGCAGUUGCAAAAUUAAUGUAUUUAUUUUCCAGCAUAAUUUUAUUAACUUCACUUUUUUUCUCUCUAGUAAAUAUCCAGUGUACUUAUGAACUCAUGUUUGGCUCUUUUAAAACCUUUUCUAAAAGCUAGAUCAGCAUUUUUCUAUUUUACAAGUUUUUUGUAUAAAAAGGUGAACAUAUGAGAUAUUGUGAGAAAUCAUUUUAAGUUUCAUUUAAAUCAUGGUGCCUCUUUUGAUACUUUCUUAAAAUUGUGCAAGAAGAAAUCAUUUUUAGUAGUGGUCAUAAAUAUUAUCCUUUUGGCAGUAAGCUAUUACUAAUUCAGCCUGAAGCUCGGUAGACAAUAUGUCUACAUGUGUUUGAGUACAUCCUGGAUACAGUUUCCCAGCUCAUGAGGGACUGAAAAUAGUCUUAUUCAUCAACCCACUAGGAUGUGAAGGGUUAAGUCUAGAUUUGGUCGCAUUGAAACCCCACAAUAUAGAAUUAAUAAAUGGCCUUCAGUAGGAAAACCUACACUAAAGCAAAUCCGAAGAAGUGGGGCAGGGGGAAAGAGGCAUUACUGGUCUUUCCUUUUGUUUUGCAAGCAUAAUUUGAUUUUCCUUUGGCUCAGAAAACUCAUUUGGGGAAAUUCUCUUUUGUGUUCAGUUUAACCUAGAAAGGUCCUCUUGAAAAACCAACAUUUUAGGAAAGUUCUUUUUUCAGGAUGGAGUAUAUUAAAAUUAAGCCAGGCUUUGACGUGAAUUAUCACUUUUCUUUAUUAUUUUGUUUUCUAUUUUGGUUUAUAGCUAUUUCUGGUUCAGUUCUGAACUUCAGCACUUAAUCAUCCUUAUCAACCAGGCUUUUGGUAGCCUAAACCGCUAUGCUGUUGUUUUUUUAAUUUAAAGAUGUAUAAGCCAAAAUUUGGAUGGGAGUGAGACAUAACUGAUUUAUAUGAAUUUUAACAGAGUUGUAUUUGUGUGUGUUUAAUAAAAUAUAUAUUUAUUCAGUACUUUCCUCAGUAUUUUAUGGGCAAAGUAAAAAUAACAAUGCAUAGUGAAAGGGCAUAUAUUACCAGCAGUAAUAAUUCAAAAUCCUGAAAAUGUUUCAUUUUUUUUGUUUUUGUUAUGCAGAAUAAACAAGGCAGAAAUGCUCUUUGAACCACU